GCUGUUGUCAGAUUACACCCACGACGGUGCGGGUCUCGGGCGUUCUGGAGAUACGUAGGGGUGAAUUUAUGUUUCCGACGAUUGCAUCUGGAGGGGUGUGUAAGACUCUGUGGCUGAAGAAAGCUAUUACGCUUCUUAUGUGGGUCAUUAUUUUAAAAAUAGCAUUUCGCUUUUAUUUGCUUGACUGCCUCUUCUCAACAAAUUUUAAGCCCGCCACUACAUGUGUUUGGUUUUGCCCUACCAGCUCUGGGGUUGGGGAGUGCACUGUUAUGGUUAUUGUUGCUCCUGUGGCCAUUCUCUUGUCAUCCCCACUUUCACAUUUUGGCGUGGUGUAUUAAUAGACUGAGUGGGAUUAAUGGGUAAAUAUGACUUUAUAGUCAGCUCUAAUCCUGGAUUCAAUAUCAGAAUUUAGAUUUUCAGCUUUGUGGAUGUUCGACAUUUUAAAAACAGUUAUUGCAAAGAGGUGAAAAUUUUGUUCUGAAGUCUUAAGGAAACAGAGAAAGUUUUUCCGUCCUUAAGUGUGGGACUUGUUUUGUGACCAACAAUAUGAAAGGCUCUGAGGUCAGCUUGGAGAAGAAAAAAAAGAUUAAGAUGCCAGUGAAGAGACUUCGUGAGGUAGUUUCUCAAAAUCAUGGAGAUCAUUUGGUUUUGCUGAAAGAUGAGUUGCCCUGUGUUCCUCCGGCAUUGUCUGCAAAUAAACGUCUUCCUGUUGGAACGGGGACUAGUUUGAAUGGAACAUCACGUGGUUCAUCAGACUUAACUUCUGCUAGAAAUUGUUACCAGCCUCUAUUAGAAAAUCCCAUGGUGUCAGAAAGUGAUUUUUCUAAAGACGUUGCAGUGCAAGUGUUGCCUUUGGAUAAAAUAGAAGAGAACAACAAGCAAAAAGCAAAUGACAUCUUCAUUUCUCAGUAUACAAUGGGACAGAAAGAUGCUCUAAGAACAGUUUUAAAGCAAAAUGUCUCACUUUGUCUCACAGGCUGGAGUGAUCACAGUGGGGUGAUCACAACUCACUGCAGUCUCUACCUCCUCAGGCUCAUGAGAUCCUCCCACCUCAGCCUCCCGAGUAGCUGGGACUACAGAGCUCAAAGCAUGCCUGUUUUUAAGGAAGUAAAGGUACAUCUGUUAGAAGAUGCAGGCAUAGAGAAGGAUGCUGUUACUCAGGAGACUAGAAUUUCACCCAGUGGAAUUGAUUCAGCUACAACCGUGGCUGCAGCAACUGCUGCUGCCAUUGCAACCGCAGCUCCGUUGAUAAAGGUGCAGAGUGAUUUGGAAGCAAAAGUCAAUUCUGUUACAGAAUUACUUAGUAAAUUACAGGAGACUGAUAAACACCUGCAACGUGUUACAGAGCAGCAAACAAGCAUUCAGAGGAAACAAGAGAAAUUACAUUGUCAUGAUCACGAAAAGCAAAUGAAUGUGUUUAUGGAGCAGCACAUAAGGCAUCUUGAAAAGUUACAACAACAACAAAUAGAUAUUCAGACUCAUUUUAUUAGUGCUGCACUCAAGACUAGUAGUUUUCAGCCUGUUAGUAUGCCCUCCUCCAGAGCAGUGGAAAAGUAUUCCGUAAAACCAGAACACCCUAAUCUUGGUAGCUGUAAUCCAUCUUUAUAUAACACAUUUGCUUCCAAACAAGCACCUUUAAAAGAAGUUGAAGAUACGAGUUUUGAUAAACAGAAAUCUCCUUUGGAGACACCAGCACCUCGCAGAUUUGCUCCUGUACCUGUUUCAAGGGAUGAUGAACUAUCAAAGAGGGAAAAUCUUUUGGAAGAAAAAGAAAAUAUGGAAGUGUCGUGUCACAGAGGAAAUGUAAGACUAUUGGAACAAAUUUUGAAUAAUAAUGAUUCUUUGACAAGAAAAAGUGAAUCAUCAAACACCACCUCACUAACUAGGUCAAAAAUAGGAUGGACUCCUGAGAAAACAAACAGAUUUCCUUCCUGUGAAGAGCUAGAAACAACUAAAGUGACUAUGCAGAAGUCUGAUGAUGUUCUUCAUGACCUUGGCCAAAAAGAGAAAGAAACAAAUAGCAUGGUCCAGCCAAAAGAAUCUCUGAGUAUGUUGAAGCUUCCAGAUCUUCCACAGAAUUCUGUUAAGCUUCAAACAACCAAUACAACAAGAUCUGUAUUGAAAGAUGCUGAGAAGAUUUUGAGAGGAGUACAAAACAAUAAAAAAGUACUUGAAGAAAACCUGGAAGCUAUUAUUCGUGCAAAAGAUGGAGCUGCCAUGUAUUCGCUUAUCAAUGCUUUAUCUACCAACAGAGAGAUGUCAGAGAAAAUUAGGAUCAGAAAGACAGUGGAUGAAUGGAUUAAAACUAUUUCUGCAGAAAUUCAGGAUGAACUGUCAAGAACAGAUUAUGAACAAAAAAGAUUUGAUCAGAAGAAUCAGAGAACCAAGAAAGGUCAGAAUAUGACUAAAGAUAUUAGAACCAACACACAAGAUAAAACUGUCAACAAAUCUGUAAUUCCAAGAAAACAUUCUCAAAAGCAAAUAGAAGAGCAUUUUAGAAAUCUACCUAUGAGGGGCAUGCCUGCUUCAAGUUUACAGAAAGAGAGAAAGGAAGGGCUUUUGAAAGCAACCACAGUAAUACAAGAUGAAGAUUAUAUGUUACAAGUCUAUGGAAAGCCAGUUUAUCAGGGCCAUCGAAGCACUCUUAAAAAAGGACCAUAUCUCAGAUUUAAUUCUCCAUCUCCUAAGUCCAGACCACAGAGACCAAAAGUAAUAGAACGAGUUAAAGGCACUAAGGUAAAGUCAAUAAGAACACAGACUGACUUCUAUGCAACAAAACCUAAGAAGAUGGAUUCUAAAAUGAAACAUUCUGUUCCUGUGUUACCUCAUGGCGAUCAGCAAUAUUUGUUCAGCCCAAGUAGAGAAAUGCCUACUUUUUCAGGUACAUUGGAAGGUCAUCUGAUUCCUAUGGCAAUUCUUUUAGGACAAACCCAAAGUAAUAGUGAUACCAUGCCACCUGCUGGAGUGAUUGUCAGCAAGCCACACCCUGUAACUGUGACUACUUCUAUUCCUCCAUCAUCUCGAAAAGUAGAAACUGGAGUAAAGAAACCUAACAUAGCCAUUGUAGAAAUGAAGUCAGAAAAAAAGGAUCCUCCUCAGCUUACUGUGCAGGUAUUACCCAGUGUAGAUAUUGACAGCAUUUCAAAUAGUAGUGCUGAUGUCCUUUCACCUCUGUCUAGCCCCAAAGAAGCAUCUCUUCCUCCUGUGCAAACUUGGAUAAAGACUCCAGAAAUUAUGAAGGUAGAUGAAGAAGAGGUGAAGUUUCCAGGAACUAACUUUGAUGAAAUAAUCGAUGUCAUACAGGAAGAAGAAAAAUGUGAUGAAAUUCCAGACUCUGAACCAAUUCUGGAGUUUAACAGAAGUGUUAAAGCUGAUUCUACAAAAUAUAAUGGUCCUCCAUUUCCGCCAGUUGCUUCUACUUUUCAGCCCACUGCUGAUAUUCUGGAUAAAGUAAUUGAGAGAAAAGAAACACUGGAAAAUAGCUUAAUUCAAUGGGUAGAGCAAGAAAUAAUGUCAAGAAUUAUCUCUGGGCUCUUUCCAGUCCAGCAACAGAUUGCACCUAGUAUCAGUGUUUCAGUCAGUGAGACAAGUGAACCACUGACUUCUGACAUUGUGGAAGGAACAAGCAGUGGCGCCCUCCAGCUUUUUGUUGAUGCUGGUGUUCCUGUGAACUCAAAUGUGAUUAAACAUUUUGUUAACGAAGCUCUUGCUGAGACCAUUGCUGUCAUGCUGGGUGACAGAGAAGCAAAGAAGCAAGGUCCUGUUGCUACAGGUGUUUCUGGGGAUGCUUCAACAAAUGAAACAUAUUUGCCGGCAAGAGUGUGCACCCCACUGCCUACCCCACAGCCUACGCCUCCUUGCUCACCUUCAUCACCUGCUAAGGAGUGUGUUUUGGUAAAGACUCCAGAUUCUUCUCCCUGUGAUUCGGAUCAUGAUAUGGCUUUUCCUGUGAAAGAAAUAUGUGCUGAAAAAGGAGAUGAUAUGCCUGCCAUCAUGCUUGUUAAUACUCCAACAGUUACCCCUACUACUACACCUCCUCCAGCGGCGGCAGUUUUUACCCCAACUUUGUCAGAUAUUUCCAUUGAUAAAUUGAAGGUAUCAAGCCCAGAGCUUCCCAAGCCAUGGGGUGAUGGAGACCUGCCACUGGAAGAAGAGAACCCUAACUCACCUCAAGAAGAACUUCAUCCAAGAGCUAUUGUAAUGUCUGUGGCUAAGGAUGAAGAACCAGAGAGUAUGGAUUUCCCUGCUCAGCCUCCACCUCCAGAGCCAGUUCCCUUUAUGCCAUUUCCUGCCGGCACCAAGGCCCCUUCCCCCUCACAGAUGCCAGGUUCUGAUUCAUCAACACUGGAGAGCACAUUGAGUGUUACUGUCACUGAAACUGAAACUUUAGAUAAACCCAUCUCUGAAGGAGAGAUUUUAUUUAGCUGUGGUCAAAAAUUGGCCCCCAAGAUUUUAGAAGAUAUAGGACUGUACCUGACAAACCUUAAUGAUAGCUUAUCCAGCACUCUGCAUGAUGCCGUUGAAAUGGAGGAUGAUCCUCCUAGUGAAGGGCAAGUGAUUAGGAUGUCCCAUAAAAAAUUUCAUGCAGAUGCAAUUCUUUCUUUUGCUAAACAAAACCAGGAGUCAGCAGUUUCCCAGCAAGCAGUCUAUCAUUCAGAGGACUUGGAAAACAGUGUGGGUGAACUUAGUGAAGGACAAAGACCCCAGCUAACAGCGGCAGCAGAGAACAUCUUAAUGGGACAUUCUCUCUAUAUGCAGCCACCUGUCACUAAUACACAGUCUUUGGAUCAACAAUGUGAUCCUAAACCAUUAUCUCGGCAAUUUGACACAGUUUCAGGUAGUAUUUAUGAAGAUUCAUGUGCUAGUCAUGGUCCAAUGAGUUUGGGAGAAUUGGAGUUGGAGCCAAAUUCUAAGCUGGUUCUUCCCACAACACUUCUGACAGCACAAGAAAAUGAUGUUAAUUUACCAGUAGCCGCUGAAGAUUUUUCCCAGUACCAACUAAAGCAAAAUCAGGAUGUUAAGCAAGUUGAACACAAACCAUCACAAAGUUACCUACGUGUUAGAAAUAAAUCUGAUAUUGCACCUUCACAGCAACAAGUUUCACCAGGUGAUAUGGAUCGGACACAAAUUGAGCUUAAUCCGUACCUCACAUGUGUAUUUUCAGGUUUGGGGGUACAUGUGAAGAAGGUUUCCUGUAUAGGUAAACUCGGGCUGUGGAGGUUUGUCAUACAGAUUAUUUCAUCACCCAGGUGGGAAAGCAGUGCCACUCUCCGCUUCACAGAUGCCCCCUGCCAAGAUGUCAGUGAUGCUGCCGUCAGUGAACCUCGAGGACUGCUCUCAGUCUCUGAGUCUCAGCACAAUGCAGGAGGACAUGGAGUCUUCGGGGGCAGAUACCUUCUGAACGGGAAGAGACAGCCAGCACAGUGUUUAUGCCACUGGUUUUAAAGUCAUUUUACCUUGGCUUAAAACCCUCUCUCAGACUGUUUGGUUUUUGAGCAUAUUCUGAAAAAAAAAUUCCAAUAUUUUAAAAUAAAACAAAAAGCAUAAUUUGGGUAUUUAAAGUUUUUAAAUAAAAUAAGUAUAAGUCAUUAUAAGUCUGAUUGUGAGUUGUUUCUUAGAAUCCUGAGAUAGCAUAGAGUAGUGAAAGGGCAUGGCUUUUGACAUCUAGGCAUUUAAUCUAUAGGUGUAAUUAUCUGUAUGUAUUUAUAAAAUUAUGUAGCUCAAGGUUAUUCAUUCUAACAUUUUUAUAACAGCAAAUAGAAAAAAUCAAAUGUCUAUCAAUAAUAGACUGGUUUUAAAGUGAUGGUACAUCAGUACAAUGGAAUACUAUGUAUUACAAAAAAAAAUUUAAAAAGUUUAUUGAUAUGGAAUAAUCUUUGAGAUGCACUGUUAAAGUGAAAAAAGCCAUGUGCAAAAUAGUGUGUGAACUAUGCAGUUGUUGAAAUUAUUUAAAAUGGGGUGGGGAGGAAUUCAAAUGUAUGGUAUGUCACAUAUUCUUACAUGUAUUUGCUUGUAAAUAUAUUAUAUAAACAAGAAACUGCUAAGUUUGUCUCCAGGGAGUAGAAUUGUUGGCUGGGUGAUAGGAGAGGCUAAGUGAUAGGAAUCAAGGAUAAUCGUGGUUACUAUGUAUUUGAACUUCAGUUGUGAUAGAAAAAAAUCAUCAGUGAGAUUAAUUUUUAUAUGCCUUAUGUAUACCAUAUAAACCUUUAUAAACCUGUGAAACAUGUAACUCUAUUACCUUUUGCAACAUAAAUACAUAAAAUUAAAGGAAAAUAAAAAGCAUUGCUUCGUAAUCAGAUACAUGUAGGUUCUAAUCCCAAUUCUGUAACUUCUUGCUUUGUGAUAGGGGCCAACGAAACGCCUUCUUAUCAGCUGUUUCAGAUUAAUGGGUUUAAUACUUAUUUUUGCAGAAUAAUGGACAUCAGUGAUUGUGUGUGGAGAUGGGGGUGGGUAGUGCCCAGCACAGUGCUUGAUACCAUGUAAGUGCUCAAUAAAUGGUGUUGUUCUUAUUAUCUUGAGGGAUUUCAGUACUGUAUAGUAGAGGGCAUAAGCACAUGAAAAGAAAGGCAGCCUAGCACUAGUGAAAAAAAUUUACCUCCCAGAAAAAUCAUUUUCUGUCACAACUGAAUUUCAAACACACAGUAAUUACAGUCAUCCUUGACUUUUUCAGCAUUUUUGUAGGUUGCUAAGUGGAUCUCAGCACUGGCAGCACAUUAGAACCUCUGGGAGCUUUAAAAAAUACUAAUGCCUGGGCCUUGUACCAAGGGAUUUCAAUUUAAUUGAUCUUGGAUGGGGUCCAGCAUUGGUAUUAAAAAAAAAAAAAGACCUUUUCAGGUAAUUUUAAUGGGCACUCAAGGCUGAGAAUUACUGAAGAGCAAUUUAGAAUUCCUUAAACUUCUAGUAGGAGCCAUUGCCUGGGGAUUUUUUUUCUCACUGAACAUAGAAGCUGCAAGAGUCUAUGGAAACUCAGAAAUGUGUCAGCCUUCCACAUGCACUUCCUCACAGCUUCUCUCAGGUAUUUGGUUACUGGAAUGUUUUAGGUUUCACUUUAGAACCCGUUUUCUUUGAUAUGGCCCUUUGGACAGUUCUGCUUAUAACAGUUUCCUUUAAACAAGUGGAAGAAAAAUUCUGCUCUGUGGAUUUUAAUUUGUUUUUGAUAUUCAUCUACAAGACUCUGGGCAAGGUGAAAGCUGGAGAAAUGUUGCUUAGUGCUGCUUCAUUUUAAACAUGACACCCCACCCCCCAACCUUGGUUUCUGGUUUUCAUAGUUUUUUCUGCCUUGGAAGGAUUUCAGCAAAAUCUUGUUUUAGUUAAAGCAUUUUUUAUUUAAAGGUGUUGGUAGAUUUUUCCUCCUAACCAUAGAAAGCCUGCCUUUUCUAACUUUAGGGUAGAAGUGUAAUCUUUGAUUUAUUCUACUCCCUGUGCACGUGAGCUUUUCUUUUAAAAAAAAUUAGUGUCCAUUCGACGGUUUCUUUUUUUUUUUUUUGAGAUGGAAUUUUGCUCGUUGCCCAGGCUGGAGUGCAAUGGCACAAUCUUGGCUCACCGCAACCUCUGCCUCCUGGUUUCAAGCGAUUCUCCUGCCUUAGCCUCCUUAGUAGCUGGGAUUACAGGCGUGCGCCACCAUGCCCGGCAAAUUUUGUAUUUUUAGUAGAGAUGGGGUUUCUCCGUGUUGGUCAGGCUAGUCCUGAACUCCCGACCUCAGGUGAUCUGCCUGCCUCAGCCUCCCAAAGUGCUGGGAUUACAGGCGUGAGCCACCGCGCCCGGCAUUCAUCUAGUAUUUUGUUUUAUAGGAUUAUUUCUGUUCAUGGUUACUCCUGUACACAUUCCUCUGCCAACCACUUCAGAUUCUUUUGGAAUAAGACGAUGUACGUAAAAACAAACUAAAUGGAACUUUUGAUUUUAUAAGCUUUAAAAUUUUUAUUUUAUAUUAAAUUUUACAAUUUCCAACUUCCGGAAUAAACUAUUUAUGAGACAUGCUAUUAAGAGACUAUCAAGAUCAAGGCUGUUACUAUUGCUGGGCUGUGACUGGACACGGUGGCUCAUGCCUGUAAUCCCAAGACUUUGGGAGGCCGAGGGUGGAUCACUUGAGCUCAGGAGUUUGAGACCAGCCUGGGCAACAUGGCAAAACCCAUCUCUACCAAAAAUACAAAAAAUUAGCUGGUCAUGGUUGCACACACCUGUAGCCCCAGCUACUCAAGAGGGUGAGGUGAGAGGAUCGCUUGAGCCCAGGAUGUCAAGACUGCAGUGAGCCGUGGUUGUGCCACUGCACUCCAGCCUGGGUGACAGAAUGAGACCGUGUCUCAAAAAAAAAAAAAAAAAAAUUGCUGAGCUAUCAUGCCUUAACACUAGGUAACGUGUUUAAAAUGUUCCUUUCUGCUGGGUGCGGGUGGCUCACACCUGUAAUCCCAGCACUUUGGGAGGCUGAGGCAGGCAGAUCACCCAAGGUUAGGAGUUCAAGACCAGUCUGGCCAACAUGGUGAAACCCCAUCUCUACUAAAAAUACAAAAAUUAGCCAGGCAUGGUGGCGUGUGCCUGUAAUCCCAGCUACUUGGGAGGCUGAGGCAGGAGAAUUGCUUCAACCCAGGAGGCAGAGGUGGCAACGAGCUGAGACUGCACCACUUAACUCCAGCCUGGGCAACAGAGUAAGACUCUGUCUCAAAAAUAAAUAAAUAAAUAAAUAAAAUGUUCCUCUGUUUUAAAUCCUAAAUUCGUUCUUUGUAUACUUUAAUAGAAUCUUGAAUAAAUAUUUUUAUUCUUAGAAGAUUA